AUUUAUCAAGUAUUUGAAUAUUUGCUACAUGCCUAGCACUGUUCCAGUCUCCUUAUCACCAGCCAUCUCAGCAAGUUGAUUAAUCUCUCUUGGGAGGAUGCAGGAAGGGAAGGGAAGCCAGGCCUCCAAGCACAGUGCCUGGCACGUAGUAGAUAUUUCACUAGGGCCAAUUCUUCCUAUACCCCCAUUCAUCAAUAGAUAAAUAGAUAAAAGGUGUCCAGGGAUGGGAGAGGUGGUUCUCAAUGUCUAUUGUACAGUCAGAGAUGACUAUGCAGUGUUUGGAAAUAGGAGAAAGUCCUGGUUUUUGGUUUUCAAUAAAAUCUCUAGCCUGCUCCUCAGAGACCGGCAUUGACCUUGCCUGGGAGCUUGUUAGGAAUGUAGUCUCAGGCUCUGUUCCAGACCCAGGGAAUCAGAACCUGCAUUUUAAUAAAAUUUUCAGGUGAUUCUGCGCACAUUGGAGAAGCACUGGAUUUCACCCUGAAGGCUGGGCAGUGAAGGAAGGGAGGGCAGCAGGUGGCUUUGCAGAUCGCUCCUCCAUGUACCAGUGAGAAGCAUUAUGAGCAUCUGGGACGGUGCUGUAACAAAUGUGAACCAGGAAAGUACAUGUCUUCUAAAUGCACUACUACCUCUGACAGUGUAUGUCUGCCCUGUGGCCCGGAUGAAUACUUGGAUAGCUGGAAUGAAGAAGAUAAAUGCUUGCUGCAUAAAGUUUGUGAUACAGGCAAGGCCCUGGUGGCCGUGGUCGCCGGCAACAGCACGACCCCCCGGCGCUGCGCGUGCACGGCUGGGUACCACUGGAGCCAGGACUGCGAGUGCUGCCGCCGCAACACCGAGUGCGCGCCGGGCCUGGGCGCCCAGCACCCGUGUACGGGUUGGAUGUCUCAACAAGGACACAGUGUGCAAACCUUGCCUUGCAGGCUACUUCUCUGAUGCCUUUUCCUCCACGGACAAAUGCAGACCCUGGACCAACUGUACCUUCCUUGGAAAGAGAGUAGAACAUCAUGGGACAGAGAAAUCCGAUGCGGUUUGCAGUUCUUCUCUGCCAGCUAGAAAACCACCAAAUGAACCCCAUGUUUACUUGCCCGGUUUAAUAAUUCUGCUUCUCUUCGCGUCUGUGGCCCUGGUGGCUGCCAUCAUCUUUGGCGUUUGCUAUAGGAAAAAAGGGAAAGCACUCACAGCUAAUUUGUGGCACUGGAUCAAUGAGGCUUGUGGCCGCCUAAGUGGAGAUAAGGAGUCCUCAGGUGACAGUUGUGUCAGUACACACACGGCAAACUUUGGUCAGCAGGGAGCAUGUGAAGGUGUCUUACUGCUGACUCUGGAGGAGAAGACAUUUCCAGAAGAUAUGUGCUACCCAGAUCAAGGUGGUGUCUGUCAGGGCACAUGUGUAGGAGGUGGUCCCUACGCACAAGGCGAAGAUGCCAGGAUGCUCUCAUUGGUCAGCAAGACCGAGAUAGAGGAAGACAGCUUCAGACAGAUGCCCACAGAAGAUGAAUACAUGGACAGGCCCUCCCAGCCCACAGACCAGUUACUGUUCCUCACUGAGCCUGGAAGCAAAUCCACACCUCCUUUCUCUGAACCCCUGGAGGUGGGGGAGAAUGACAGUUUAAGCCAGUGCUUCACGGGGACACAGAGCACAGUGGGUUCAGAAAGCUGCAACUGCACUGAGCCCCUGUGCAGGACUGAUUGGACUCCCAUGUCCUCUGAAAACUACUUGCAAAAAGAGGUGGACAGUGGCCAUUGCCCGCACUGGGCAGCCAGCCCCAGCCCCAACUGGGCAGAUGUCUGCACAGGCUGCCGGAACCCUCCUGGGGAGGACUGUGAACCCCUCGUGGGUUCCCCAAAACGUGGACCCUUGCCCCAGUGCGCCUAUGGCAUGGGCCUUCCCCCUGAAGAAGAAGCCAGCAGGACGGAGGCCAGAGACCAGCCCGAGGAUGGGGCUGAUGGGAGGCUCCCAAGCUCAGCGAGGGCAGGUGCCGGGUCUGGAAGCUCCCCUGGUGGCCAGUCCCCUGCAUCUGGAAAUGUGACUGGAAACAGUAACUCCACGUUCAUCUCCAGCGGGCAGGUGAUGAACUUCAAGGGCGACAUCAUCGUGGUCUACGUCAGCCAGACCUCGCAGGAGGGCGCGGCGGCGGCUGCGGAGCCCAUGGGCCGCCCGGUGCAGGAGGAGACCCUGGCGCGCCGAGACUCCUUCGCGGGGAACGGCCCGCGCUUCCCGGACCCGUGCGGCGGCCCCGAGGGGCUGCGGGAGCCGGAGAAGGCCUCGAGGCCGGUGCAGGAGCAAGGCGGGGCCAAGGCUUGAGCGCCCCCCAUGGCUGGGAGCCCGAAGCUCGGAGCCAGGGCUCGCGAGGGCAGCACCGCAGCCUCUGCCCCAGCCCCGGCCACCCAGGGAUCGAUCGGUACAGUCGAGGAAGACCACCCGGCAUUCUCUGCCCACUUUGCCUUCCAGGAAAUGGGCUUUUCAGGAAGUGAAUUGAUGAGGACUGUCCCCAUGCCCACGGAUGCUCAGCAGCCCGCCGCACUGGGGCAGAUGUCUCCCCUGCCACUCCUCAAACUCGCAGCAGUAAUUUGUGGCACUAUGACAGCUAUUUUUAUGACUAUCCUGUUCUGUGGGGGGGGGGGUCUGUUUUCCCCCCAUAUUUGUAUUCCUUUUCAUAACUUUUCUUGAUAUCUUUCCUCCCUCUUUUUUAAUGUAAAGGUUUUCUCAAAAAUUCUCCUAAAGGUGAGGGUCUCUUUCUUUUCUCUUUUCCUUUUUUUUUUCUUUUUUUGGCAACCUGGCUCUGGCCCAGGCUAGAGUGCAGUGGUGCGAUUAUAGCCCGGUGCAGCCUCUAACUCCUGGGCUCAAGCAAUCCAAGUGAUCCUCCCACCUCAACCUUCGGAGUAGCUGGGAUCACAGCUGCAGGCCACGCCCAGCUUCCUCCCCCCGACUCCCCCCCCAGAGACACGGUCCCACCAUGUUACCCAGCCUGGUCUCAAACUCCCCAGCUAAAGCAGUCCUCCAGCCUCGGCCUCCCAAAGUACUGGGAUUACAGGCGUGAGCCCCCACGCUGGCCUGCUUUACGUAUUUUCUUUUGUGCCCCUGCUCACAGUGUUUUAGAGAUGGCUUUCCCAGUGUGUGUUCAUUGUAAACACUUUUGGGAAAGGGCUAAACAUGUGAGGCCUGGAGAUAGUUGCUAAGUUGCUAGGAACAUGUGGUGGGACUUUCAUAUUCUGAAAAAUGUUCUAUAUUCUCAUUUUUCUAAAAGAAAGAAAAAAGGAAACCCGAUUUAUUUCUCCUGAAUCUUUUUAAGUUUGUGUCGUUCCUUAAGCAGAACUAAGCUCAGUAUGUGACCUUACCCGCUAGGUGGUUAAUUUAUCCAUGCUGGCAGAGGCACUCAGGUACUUGGUAAGCAAAUUUCUAAAACUCCAAGUUGCUGCAGCUUGGCAUUCUUCUUAUUCUAGAGGUCUCUCUGGAAAAGAUGGAGAAAAUGAACAGGACAUGGGGCUCCUGGAAAGAAAGGGCCCGGGAAGUUCAAGGAAGAAUAAAGUUGAAAUUUUAAUUUGCAUUUUUUUUGUCUAGAUAAGAAUAGCGUGAAUAGAUCCUCUUUUAUUCGUAAAUAAUCGUGCAUCUGUGGGUUAGCCUUGUAGAAGUGGAAAACAUUCCAUUUUCCAAUGCAUUUAAAUGUAAAGCCAAAUCUGCAUGUUGUGAAUUUAAGAAAACUUAUUAUCCUAAAGGUGCCUUUCUCUUGGCAUCAUCCCGCUUGUGAGAAGCCUAGAGGACGCUCCAGGUGGAAGGAAAUCCCCUGGGUGGUUUUAUCUUUUGUUACCCAGUGAGCACUGGUUCCCCGCAAAUACUGGGGAAAAGCAAAAAUACACAAGCAAGUUAAAAUUAAUUUUGCACAUCUGGGAGGUUAUAAAAGAAAGCACUAAUAGUAGUCACUGCCCAGACUUUACUGGCCACAAAUGCCCAGCUGAAGAGCAUGACUGUGGAUCACUGGUUUUUCCCUCCUGCUGGAAAUGCUGGGGUGGUAGCGGUCGAUUAGGAUUUUCAGUGGAGAAGCACAGGACAGUUCUGUAAUUUAUGGGACUCCUUAGCCAACAUAAAGAACUGCAGGAAAUAACUGCACAGCCAGGAGGAUCCGUUGGUGGGAAUUUACCGUCAUUCCUGCCCUUUUAUUUAACAUCAUCCACAGAGAGAUGUUAUACAAAUGGAGGAAACCAUUAUACCUUUUGAUAUGGAAUAUAUUACAGAGUUACAGUUCACAAAGUAGAAUGCUGAGCUGAAAACCCGAGUUUCUGCUGUGACUGUCAUCUCACUGAGCACUUCGCUUUUCUUUGCUUUUAUUUUUUCCUUCUAUAAAAAGGCAAUAAUGAUAAUUUAUAAUAGUUUCCCUACCCAGAGAUAUUAGAAGUAUGCUACAGUGAAUGUUAAAGUACCUUGAGAUCCUUAAAUCAAAGGUGCUAUAUACAUAAGUAAGACUCUACUUUCAGAAAAAGGUAAUAUUAUUUCCUGCACUGAUCCCUACUAAUUCUAUAUUGAUCCAAAGGCAACUCAAUGCUAAAAAAUGUAUAGAAAAUAUAAGUCUGUGUCUGUGUACUGUAGAGAUGUAUGUGACAAGUGUAAACAAAAUGAACUGAAGCAGUAAUGAACAGUUAUUAGGGGGAACAUGAUAAAGAGAUUAUAUUAAGCUUAUGUUUCACCAUAAAAUCCUUUUUAUGGCUUACUAAAACCGAGCUCACUGUAAAAUCAUGAUCCAACUUAUUGCUAAUCUUUAUGAUAUGCUUAUUCCUAAUCUUUAUGGUAUGGUGUCAACCGUUCAUUUGUAUCUUAUUGCUCAUUCCCUGGACCACAGACUAGGGACAGAAAAUACUUGCUUUAAUAAUAUAUAUGCUGUUGAUUUCACAAAAAUUUAUUAAAAUACAGCCUGGGUACCCAGUGAAAGAGCUGAAAUGGAAAUGGAGUAUCAUGUUUCCUACUCACAUUUUACUCAGCUGUCGGAAGGAAGAAUGAAUUUCUCAAGAGCAGUUUGAAUGUGUUAGAUCAGAACCUUCAUGUGGUGGGGAAAAUGGGAUUAUUUCAGUGUAACAAACCACCCAAAGACUUAGUGGCUUAAAAUAGUCACCAUUGGCCAGGCACAGCGGUUCAUGCCUCCCAGUGCUUUGGGAGGCCAAGGCAGGAGGAUCACUUGAGGACAGUAGUUAGAGAUCAAACUGGGCAAUGGAGUGAGACCUCGUCUCUACAAAAAAUACAAAACUUAUCUGGGCACGGUGGUGUGCACCUGCAGUCCUGGCUACUCAGGAGGCUGAGGCAGGAGGAUGCUUGAGUCCAGGAGUUCAAGGUUACUGUGAGCUUUGAUUGGGUCAGUGCACUCCAGUGUAAAAAAACAAAAAUAAAAACCACCACUUAUUUAGCUCCCAAUUCUAUGGGUUGGAUCAGCUUGGGUGGUUCUUCAGGCCUGGUCCCUCCUGGCCUGGUUUGCUUACCCAUUUACAAUGACCCGGCUAGUUGGCCGGGCCAGGCUGUGUGCUCUCCACCUGUCUCCCAUCCUUCCAGCCACCUAGCUGGGCAUGCUCUCAUGGUGGUGUCGAGCCUGAGAACAAGCAGAAACCUGCCAGGCUUCUUGAGGCCUAGGCUCUAACUGGCAUGCUGUCACUUCUGCCACAUUCUGUGGGCCAAAGCAGGUCACAAAGGCAGCCCAGAUCCAAGGGAUGGGGGAGCAGCAUAUCCCCCCAUGGGAAGAGUUGCGGAAUGAGAGGGUAGGGGGUGGACACACAGAGGGGAAGAUGGCCCCCUUGCCAUCUGUCCACCACAGGGCACUGCGUGGAGUAAAAUGCUGCAGAGAAGAGUGCAUUCUGGGAAAAAAAGAGGAACAUAUCCCAGCCCCUAACCAGUGAGUAGCUCCUUCUCUGGUGAUUGAAUUCCCUUAAUGCACAGCACUAUAGAUUCCCACAAUGAAAGGGACACCCACGUUCAUAUUUAAGUGCUGUGUCAAAAUUCUUUCCAGAGCCAAAUAUAGGUGAUUUGGGAAUUGAGCCUACUGUACUGCUUCCACAUUCCUUUGGCACAGAAAACUGAAAAGUCACAACUUCUAAAAUCAAGAAAACUGGUGAGAUACCUUGGGGUAGAGAAACCUGCAUAUAAACAGAUAAAAGAUCGAGUGUUCACCCUUCACCUCAGCUCAACAAACAAACUCUUGUUACGAUUAUACAAGGGUGAGCUUGAGCAAAGGUGCUGUCUUUGGUGGAAGAAACGUAGUUUUGAGUUGUUUGCUCUUUGACAGUCUCUGAUGGCAUGUGAGUCUGGUGCAUUGCUGUGGGCUGCGCUGGGCACAAGUUGCAUAACCCGCUUUUGGAAGAGGAGACAAAGCAUUCAAAGCCCUAAACACUCUGUUGGUGAAUCAUCAUGUUUAUUGAGUGUGCUUUUAGUGGCAGGGCCCUGAGCACCUGGGAAAGGAGAUGAGGAGCGCUGGAGGGUUCGGAGCAGAGAAGACGAGACAAUGCUCUGCUCCAAGCGCCAGAGGAGGCUUCUGGGAAGGGGCUGUCUGUGGAAUUUCUGACCCCCAGAGCCCUGCUGGUGAAGUCUUGCAACCACUAAAGCUUUGCCAGAGAAGAGGAGGGACCUGACACUGGGCAGUGGCGGUGCCAGCAGUGAGCACAGGCGGGGUCUAGGUGGGAUCACUGAAGCCAAGCCAAGUGGUGCAGGGGGAGCCGCCCUGGACCAACACCCCCAUGGCUGCCCCACUGCGGAACUGCCUACUGCGGCAAAACAAUCCUAUGUCCCCCAAGGUUUCAACAAAGAGGAGGACCGAAUAAAUGUCCCAGUGGGCAGGCACACCCACAAGACUUGCUGCUCCUCCUGACCCACCCGCAUGGCUCUGCACAGCUGUGAGUCCAGUUUUCUCUCUUCCUACCUCCCUCUUACCCAGUUAUCCUGACCCCAGGGUGAGGUUGAAACUCAUGCUAGGCUAACAUCUCUUUCCUUCAUCCCAUUCAUAAAACUGGCAUACAGGAAUGUUUUAAAAAAAUCUUUAAGAUUACCAGGAGUAUAAAAGUUAAAAUGACAAAAUUACAGGCCUGUUACCAGAUCUUCGUACUAACCAAGGAGCUGGUGACACUACCCUCUUCCCUGUGUGAUAGAAAAUGCAGACGUUUUGCAGGCAGACCUGGUUCAUGACUCAGCGCUGUGACUUGUGGACUUAUCUUGUGCAGCUACAUCACUUCUUAGCCUUGUUUUCAACAUGCGUAAGCAGAAGGUACUAAUAUUAGUCUUUAGGGCUGGUUUGAGGAUGACGUGAGAUGAGAGACAACCAAGCACUCACUGGCAGUUCCUAGAAGAUUCCAGUAGUAGAGAUCUGACUGUCCUACACUACUUUCCCUCCCUGUCUCUGACACUUGUUCAUUCCUGGGCUCAGGAGCCAUCUCAGUCAUCAUGUCGGACCACGUAACUAUAACCAAGCUCUGCUGCCCACCUGGGACACCUUCCCACUCUUUGCAACUAGGUCGGAGGGACGCACCUUCUCCACAGUUGACAGGACUGUUAUGGUUGACCCAAAAGUUGUCAUCUUCUGACAUGACACACUGAGGGAAGUAGACUUACCCAAUAUAACUUCACAUUAUACUGUCUUAAAAGACUAUGAUUAAAAUGGGCAUCAGUGUAGGCAACAUGUAGGGCGCAAAGAAUAGCCAGAUGUGAAGGUUGAAAGGCUAUGUGGGCUAGUUUGUCAUGGUAUUCCUGGUGCCUCUCCCCGUUUGGGAAGAAUAACACAUUGACCACCGGCUCAGAGGAGGUGGCAUUAUAGGUCCAGGCCCCUUCAGGAGGGCACUGGAGUCAAUGAAAGCUUUUGCUCUCACCCAGGCUCUUGGUUUCUCACGGGCAGGGGUAGCCCAGGAAACAAAGGCUGUAUAGACUUUAAGUCGUGAGAAAAACGACAUUCUUAUGGUGAGGCUCUUAGAGACUGUCUCCAUUUAAGCAGCAGCAGUAAAACAUCUUACCCUAAAAUGAAGAAGCAAAUCCAUUUUUAUUGGCUUUUAUAGCCUCUCUCUUUCAAUGACAAAGAAACCAUUAAAAUGAAUGUUUAAAGUUCUUAGAAGAGCUUUCUCUAAAUAUUUACUCUGUCAGUGGAAAAAUAAACAUUUUUUACAUCGGGUCUAUUGAGUUUGUUAUAUACAGUAAAAUUCACCCUUUUUAGAUAUAUAGUUUUAUGAGUUUUAACAAAAAUACAUAGUUGUGUAACCACCACCAUCACAAUCAAGAUAUAGAAUAUUUCAACAUCCCAAAGUUCCCAUUUCCCUUUUCAGUCAAUCCCUUCCCCACUACCCCUAGCCCCUGGCAACCAUUAUCUGUUCUCUCUUCCCAUAGUUUCACCUUUUCCAAUUUGUCGUGUAGAGUUACACAGCUCAUAGCCAUUUGAGUCUGGCUUCUUUCCACAUAAUGUCCUUGAGAUCCAUCGGUGGGUACACCAGUAGUUCCAUUUUUUUUCUGAGUAGUAGUCCAUUGUAUGGAUGUACUGCGGUUUAUUCACCAACAUAUGGGUUCUUUCCUGUUUGGGGAGAUUACAAAUAAAGCUACUAUAAAAA